GGAGCAUGCGCACUGGCAGGCCCUCGCUCAGCCUUUGGAGACCAUGCGCAGGCGCGGUGCACUGUGCGCGGGCACCACGGCGGUUUUUCGACGCUGGCGGUGGACGCAGGCAGCAUGGACCACGGUUGCUGGGCGGAUGGGGAGCGUCUAUGGUCAGUUGCCUUAGAAGUGGUGAGAUGGGAAGCUGCAGUUGGAAGACCCUGGAGGAUGCCUGACAAGGGGAUGUCUGACACAUGAUUGGAGCUCUUUUUGAAAUGUUUCUUGCCCUUCCUGGAGCAGAGGAGCCAUUAUUUAUGCAGUGAUUAUGCCUGUCAUCGCUGGUGGUAUCCUGGCGGCCUUGCUCCUGCUGAUAGUUGUCGUGCUCUGUCUUUACUUCAAAAUACACAACGCGCUAAAAGCUGCAAAGGAACCUGAAGCUGUGGCUGUAAAAAAUCACAACCCAGACAAGGUGUGGUGGGCCAAGAACAGCCAGGCCAAAACCAUUGCCACGGAGUCUUGUCCUGCCCUGCAGUGCUGUGAAGGAUAUAGAAUGUGUGCCAGUUUUGAUUCCCUGCCACCUUGCUGUUGCGACAUAAAUGAGGGCCUCUGAGUUAGGAAAGGUGGGCACAAAAAUCUUCAUGAGCAAUACUUCUUAGUAGAUUGUUUUGUUAUUCAAAUCAAGUUCUAGUGUUUUUAUGUGAGAUUAUAUAAUUUACAGUGUUGUUUUAUAUACUUUUGAAUAAAUGUACACUAUUAAAAAUAA